AACGAUGCUUGAGAGCUAAGCUGGAAGGACGUGGGGUGCUUAUCCCUCGUAGAAAUGCCUGCCAAUGCUUUCUCAUUUGGACCCAAACUCCAGAUCGGGAGCAGUCUUAUAGCUGGAUCAGCUACCAAGAGAAAUUCUAAAGCAAGAAGAGAAAAGCAUUUCAAUUUGGGACAUUUAUUUGCACCUGGAAAUGGGGAAUGGGCUAUCAGACCAGACUUCUAUCCUGUCCAACCUGCCUUCAUUCAGUCCUUCCACAUUGUUAUUCUGGGUUUGGACUGUGCUGGAAAGACAACUGUCUUAUACAGGCUGCAGUUCAAUGAAUUUGUAAAUACCAUACCUACCAAAGGAUUUAACACUGAGAAAAUUAAGGUAAGCUUGGGAAAUUCUAAAACAGUCACUUUUCACUUCUGGGAUGUAGGUGGUCAGGAGAAAUUAAGGCCACUGUGGAAGUCAUAUACCAGAUGCACAGAUGGCAUUGUAUUUGUUGUGGACUCUGUUGAUGUCGAAAGGAUGGAAGAAGCCAAAACUGAACUUCACAAAAUAACUAGGAUAUCAGAAAAUCAAGGAGUCCCUGUACUUAUAGUUGCUAACAAACAAGACUUGAGGAACUCAUUGUCUCUUUCAGAAAUUGAGAAAUUGUUAGCAAUGGGUGAACUGAGCUCAUCAGCUCCUUGGCAUUUGUAGCCUACCUGUGCAAUCAUAGGAGAUGGCCUAAAGGAAGGACUUGAGAAACUACAUGAUAUGAUCAUUAAAAGAAAAAUUUUGCGGCAACAGAAAAAGAAAAGAUGAAUAUCAAUAUCUAUUAUAUCUGUGUGGAGUAGGUUUUCUCUGGUCUGAUUUUGACAAAUAGAAGAGUGUCUACAGCGUGGUUUGCCUGUCUGCCCUCCUGGAUGCUAUUAAAGCUUUGUUUUGUUGAACAAUCAGAUGCCCAACUCUGUUGCCUUGUGGAAGAUGAGUAAAUGCAGUGCUUCUUAAAGUGGUUUCUUCUCCCUACCCCACACAUCUUUUGGUACUACCAUUUGGGGAAGCCAAGCAAGGAUAGUAAAUUGAUCAGAACACAGUUGUGGGAAUUUGGCCUGAAGUUAGUGAAAUAAAACUUUAAAGAGUG